ACUCUUUGGAUGCACAACAAUGGCCACACAUCGAGAUUGAAAUGAAGGGAUAAAAACAUUCCUAUAAAUUCGAAGGCAAGUUUUGCUGACUAGAAAAACAAGCCAAUAAUUUGAAAUGGUGUGCCCGAAUGGAUACGACCCAGGGGGCCGACAUCUACUGCUGUUUAUUAUAAUUCUAGCAGCUUGGGAGGCAGGGAGAGGCCAGCUCCACUACUCGGUCCCCGAGGAGGCUAAACAUGGCAACUUCGUGGGCCGCAUCGCGCAGGACCUGGGGCUGGAGCUGGCGGAGCUGGUGCCGCGCCUGUUCCGGGCGGUGUGCAAAUUCCGUGGGGAUCUUCUGGAGGUAAAUCUGCAGAAUGGCAUUUUGUUUGUGAAUUCUCGGAUCGACCGCGAGGAGCUGUGCGGGCGGAGCGCGGAGUGCAGCAUCCACCUGGAGGUGAUCGUGGAAAGGCCGCUGCAGGUUUUCCAUGUGGACGUGGAGGUGAAGGACAUUAACGACAACCCUCCGGUGUUCCCAGCGACACAAAGGAAUCUGUUCAUCGCGGAAUCCAGGCCGCUUGACUCUCGGUUUCCACUAGAGGGCGCGUCCGAUGCAGAUAUCGGGGAGAACGCCCUGCUCACUUACAGACUGAGCCCCAAUGAGUAUUUCUUCCUGGACGUGCCAACCAGCAACCAGCAGGUAAAACCUCUUGGACUUGUAUUACGGAAACUUUUAGACAGAGAAGAAACUCCGGAGCUUCAUUUAUUGCUCACGGCCACCGAUGGAGGCAAACCCGAGCUGACUGGCACCGUUCAAUUACUCAUCACGGUACUGGACAACAAUGACAAUGCCCCAGUGUUCGACAGAACCCUGUAUACGGUGAAAUUACCAGAAAACGUUUCUAUCGGAACGCUGGUGAUUCACCCCAAUGCCUCAGAUUUAGACGAAGGCUUGAAUGGGGAUAUUAUUUACUCCUUCUCCAGUGAUGUUUCUCCAGAUAUAAAAUCCAAGUUCCACAUGGACCCCUUAAGUGGGGCAAUCACAGUGAUAGGACAUAUGGAUUUUGAAGAAAGUAGAGCACACAAGAUCCCAGUCGAGGCUGUCGAUAAAGGCUUCCCACCCCUGGCUGGUCAUUGUACAGUUCUUGUGGAAGUUGUGGAUGUAAAUGACAAUGCUCCACAGUUGACUCUCACUUCCCUGUCUCUCCCUAUUCCAGAGGACGCCCAACCAGGUACCGUCAUCACAUUGAUUAGCGUGUUUGACCGAGAUUUUGGAGUCAACGGACAGGUUACCUGCUCCCUGACGCCCCGCGUUCCCUUCAAGUUGGUGUCCACCUUCAAGAAUUACUAUUCAUUGGUGCUGGACAGCGCUCUGGACCGCGAGAGUGUGUCCGCCUAUGAGCUGGUGGUUACCGCGCGGGACGGGGGCUCGCCUUCUCUGUGGGCCACUGCUAGCGUGUCCGUGGAGGUGGCCGACGUGAACGACAACGCCCCGGCGUUCGCGCAGCCCGAGUAUACGGUGUUCGUGAAGGAGAACAACCCGCCGGGCUGCCACAUCUUCACUGUGUCGGCGGGGGACGCGGACGCGCAGAAGAACGCGCUGGUGUCCUACUCGCUGGUGGAGCUGCGGGUGGGCGAGCGCGCGCUGUCGAGCUACGUGUCAGUGCACGCGGAGAGCGGCAAGGUGUACGCGCUGCAGCCGUUGGACCACGAGGAGCUGGAGCUGUUGCAGUUCCAGGUGAGCGCGCGCGAUGCGGGCGUGCCGCCUCUGGGCAGCAACGUGACGCUGCAGGUGUUCGUGCUGGACGAGAACGACAACGCGCCGGCACUGCUGGCGCCUCGGGUGGGUGGCACUGGUGGCGCAGUGAGAGAGCUUGUGCCGCGGUCUGUGGGCGCGGGCCAUGUGGUGGCGAAGGUACGUGCAGUUGACGCUGACUCAGGCUACAACGCGUGGCUUUCGUAUGAGUUGCAACCGGUGGCGGCCGGUGCGAGCAUCCCGUUCCGCGUGGGGCUGUACACUGGUGAGAUCAGCACGACACGAGCCCUAGAUGAGACGGACGCACCGCGCCACCGCCUUCUGGUGCUUGUGAAGGACCACGGGGAGCCCUCGCUGACAGCCACAGCCACCGUGCUGGUGUCGCUGGUGGAAAGCGGCCAGGCACCAAAGGCGUCGUCGCGGGCAUCGUUGGGCAUUGCAGGCCCAGAGACCGAGCUGGUGGAUGUCAACGUGUACCUGAUCAUCGCCAUCUGCGCGGUGUCCAGUCUGUUGGUGCUUACCCUGCUGCUGUACACGGCGUUGCGGUGCUCAGCGCCGUCCUCUGAGGGCGCAUGUAGUUUGGUAAAGCCCACUCUGGUGUGCUCCAGCGCGGUGGGGAGCUGGUCAUUCUCCCAGCAGAGGCGGCAGAGGGUGUGCUCUGGGGAGGGCCCACCCAAGACAGACCUCAUGGCCUUCAGUCCCAGCCUUCCUCAGGGUCCAUCCUCUACAGACAAUCCACGACAGCCCAACCCUGACUGGCGUUACUCUGCCUCCCUGAGAGCAGGCAUGCACAGCUCUGUGCACCUAGAGGAGGCUGGCAUUCUACGGGCUGGUCCAGGAGGGCCUGAUCAGCAGUGGCCAACAGUAUCCAGUGCAACACCAGAACCAGAGGCAGGAGAAGUGUCCCCUCCAGUCGGUGCGGGUGUCAACAGCAACAGCUGGACCUUUAAAUACGGACCAGGCAACCCCAAACAAUCCGGUCCCGGUGAGUUGCCCGACAAAUUCAUUAUCCCAGGAUCUCCUGCAAUCAUCUCCAUCCGGCAGGAGCCUACUAACAGCCAAAUUGACAAAAGUGACUUCAUAACCUUCGGCAAAAAGGAGGAGACCAAGAAAAAGAAGAAAAAGAAGAAGGGUAACAAGACCCAGGAGAAAAAAGAGAAAGGGAACAGCACGACUGACAACAGUGACCAGUGAGGUCCUCAAAUGGAAACAAGCCACUUAGCCAGUUUUUGUAAUAAUGGCAAAUCUCUCCCAUGUAGCAAUUCCCUGCUCCUUUUUCCUAUCUACAUGAGCCCUCUUAGAGACCUCAGAAAUCUGCAGAAAGUUCCCUGUGUCUGUCUAGAACGCAUUUAACAGGUUUUGUCGUAAAAGCUUUACUAAGUCUGGUGUUAACUCUUUCUCUCCACUCUGGCUUGUUUUCAGAACCUAAAAAGCAGACCCAAGUUUCCUUUCUCCUCCGCCGCAAAGGAGAGGCUUCCCAGCCCCGCCAGUGAGAGGUUGGACUCUCUGCCCUGUGCUCCGGGGAUCCUGUCUUGAUGACACUUGCAGGGCAGGCUGAAAAGUUUUGAGAUUGAGCAGCUUGGGAGUUUGUGGCCACUGGGUAUGUGUGGCUACCGCGGGUAUGCGAGUGCCAGAUAUUGGCUGAGACGAGCCAGCUUAGACUAAUUGGUACAAGGAAGGCAAGAAAACAAAGACAAAUAAACAGCGGAAGUUAUCAGUAUGGAGGGGAAGUGUAAACUUAAAGGGACCAGACUUUCUAAAUCUUACAACUCAAGAGGUGGCAGCCACCCUCUAGGAGACAAAACUACCCCCACUGACAAGGCUUUAGGAGACCCUAAAGUCUGUUGGCUGUGACGUCAUUAUACCUAAAAUCUGCAUCAUACCUGCAAGCCAACAGUUCAGUGUUUUAACAGAGAACCACCCUGGGAAACAGAAGCAGAUCUGAUGUGUUUCCUAUACAUGUCCUGUGCUCACUUUAUUAAAAAUUCUUUUGCACACAAUGUUUAUGAAAAGGCCAGAUCCUUUUCCAAUACUUAUGCAAAAGCAAAAGAAAACCCCGACACCUCACCUUUCGCUGUUUGUUGUUUCAUAGAUUUAUUUAAAAAAAGAGAAAGUCUAUAGCUAUAAAUCUUUAAAGAGAAAUAUGAAUACAAUUCCCCUAAACUCUCCUCAAAAGAGAAUUCAGUCUACAGCCAUUUAAAUGAUCAUUGCUGCUACAGAAGUGCUUUAAGAGAAUUGCCUGAAACAUCUGUAUUAUAUCGGCCACCUGCCAAUCACAGCUUUACUCUUUCAGGUCACUCUGGGGCUGCCUCUUGCAUGUAUUACUAAAUAAAAUGAUCUCUCUUUCUCUCUCUCUCUCUCUUUUCUAAGAAACAAUUAUGUGCACUUUGAUACACAACCUUCUCUAACCAACUAUAUAUCAAGACCCAAAAAUUGAAGAAAAAUAUUGUUUUCUCAUACAGUGAGCAGAUUUUUCAAUCUACUAAUUCUGUGACUUGUCUUGGUGUGCUAGCCUACACCUUCUCUUUGGUUUAGUUUUCCUUUUCUAUAACACUCUGAAUUGCUAAUCUUACUAACACCUAUGAUGUUACCUGAAAUCAAUCUCCCAUAUGUAUGCUGUAUGCUAUGCUAAGACUCCUGAAAUAUACUUACUCUGUGCUUGUGUAUGUGAAUGUUAAUGCAACUAUUACCUAGAGUGAACUUUAAGCUUUAUUGUUGAAUGUAAUUCCAUUAUAUUUCCUUUUGUACACCUGUGAAAAAGUGGAGUAGUGUUUUUUUAACCAUUGUUAAUCAGCUUUUGUGUAUGAAAGACACAGUAAAAUUUCUUUCUUAAAUCAAGAUACUGGUGAUUCAAGGAAUUUUAUUUAUGGUCCAGCCAAGAGCCAUCUCGUGCCAAGACUUCUGCUGGCAAGGGAAUGGAUAAAGCUGUUUUGUUCUAGUAACAAUUUUGGAAUGAAUACUGACAAUAUUCCAUGAGGGUGUGCAAGCACAAAUUUUACCAAUCUGACCUCUUUGAAGUUGCAGAAUGCUUUGAAAUUCUAAUGGUAUCUGAAAUAUCAGCUCAUAGAAAGUAACAAAAUUUGCUGUCACCUUAAAUAAGACAUUUUAAUUUUGUUAUAAUGUACAAUUUAGAAGUUUGAUUAAUUAUAUUAUCUAUUUAGGCAUUAAUAUAAAAGAGGUAGGAGUCUGUUAUUUAAAAAAAGCAUUAAAUUUAAAAAAAAACUGUCUUGUCUACUUUUAGCUUCAUUCUCCCAUAUUUUGAAGGGUGUGUAACUUCAGCUCUGCAGGAUUGCAUGGGGUAAAACUUGUUACCAACACAUGUGAACCAUUGCUACAUUGUAGGUUGUGAUCAUUUUGCCCCACUGAAGCCCAUGUAUCUGACCUUACGUGCCUUUUGAACUAGGAGAAUCGGGCUAAUUUAUUAAUGAUGAUAAUUAUAAUGUAUCUGUACAGCACUUUUUACAUUUGCGAAGUGCUUUCCAAUCCAUGUUAGUUACUAGUUAUUACAGCUGUAAGGAUAAAACACGUCAUGUGGAUUCAUUUUGAAUUGGUGCUAUUGGUAUUUCCUCUGUUAUUGCUAAUAAAUGAAAAUGGUGGUAUGAAA